AGGGCAGCUCAAGACGCUGAGGUGGUGGCUGCGGCCUUUGAACAAGUAAGUGAGCCACCCUCGGAGACCCCCGCGCUGGGGACGGGAGGCCGGCGAGCCUCGGGACCUCUGAAAGCCUUGAGGAGGCGCGGGGGUGAGUGCGGCCCUGAGGAAACCCAGGUGCCCCGCCCCUCCCUUUCUUCCUGGCCCGCGCCUCGCCUACCCCUCCCCCGACCCUGGCGGGCCCCCGGCUCUGGGCCCGGACCCCUGGGGUAGCUAGUCUGCCACGAACCAGCCGCGCGCUUCUGCCCUUGUCGGUUUAGGAAACUGGGAAGUUCCCUGGUCCUGCUCCCCAGCCCGCAGAGGGGACACUGAGGCCCACGGUAGGUGGUCCUCUCCUCACCCGAGUCUCCACACAGACACCAUGGCCGAGCCUCUGAAGGAGGAAGACGGCGAGGACGGCUCUGCGGAGCCCCCCGGGCCCGUGAAGGCCGAACCCGCCCACACCGCUGCCUCUGUAGCGGCCAAGAACCUGGCCCUGCUUAAAGCCCGCUCCUUCGAUGUGACCUUUGACGUGGGCGACGAGUACGAGAUCAUCGAGACCAUAGGCAACGGGGCCUAUGGAGUGGUGUCCUCCGCCCGCCGCCGCCUCACCGGCCAGCAGGUGGCCAUCAAGAAGAUCCCUAAUGCUUUCGAUGUGGUGACCAAUGCCAAGCGGACCCUCAGGGAGCUGAAGAUCCUCAAGCACUUUAAACACGACAACAUCAUCGCCAUCAAGGACAUCCUGAGGCCCACCGUGCCCUAUGGCGAAUUCAAAUCUGUCUACGUGGUCCUGGACCUGAUGGAAAGCGACCUGCACCAGAUCAUCCACUCCUCACAGCCCCUCACACUGGAACACGUGCGCUACUUCCUGUACCAACUGCUGCGGGGCCUGAAGUACAUGCACUCGGCUCAGGUCAUCCACCGUGACCUGAAGCCCUCCAACCUAUUGGUGAAUGAGAACUGUGAGCUCAAGAUUGGUGACUUUGGUAUGGCUCGUGGCCUGUGCACCUCGCCCGCUGAACAUCAGUACUUCAUGACUGAGUAUGUGGCCACGCGCUGGUACCGUGCGCCCGAGCUCAUGCUCUCUUUGCAUGAGUAUACACAGGCUAUUGACCUCUGGUCUGUGGGCUGCAUCUUUGGUGAGAUGCUGGCCCGGCGCCAGCUCUUCCCAGGCAAAAACUAUGUACACCAGCUACAGCUCAUCAUGAUGGUGCUGGGUACCCCAUCACCAGCCGUGAUUCAGGCUGUGGGGGCUGAGAGGGUGCGGGCCUAUAUCCAGAGCUUGCCACCACGCCAGCCUGUGCCCUGGGAGACAGUGUACCCAGGUGCCGACCGCCAGGCCCUAUCACUGCUGGGUCGCAUGCUGCGUUUUGAGCCCAGCGCUCGCAUCUCAGCAGCUGCUGCCCUUCGCCACCCUUUCCUGGCCAAGUACCAUGAUCCUGAUGAUGAGCCUGACUGUGCCCCGCCCUUUGACUUUGCCUUUGACCGCGAAGCCCUCACUCGGGAGCGCAUUAAGGAGGCCAUUGUGGCUGAAAUUGAGGACUUCCAUGCAAGGCGUGAGGGCAUCCGCCAACAGAUCCGCUUCCAGCCUUCUCUACAGCCUGUGGCUAGUGAGCCUGGCUGUCCAGAUGUUGAAAUGCCCAGUCCCUGGGCUCCCAGUGGGGACUGUGCCAUGGAGUCUCCACCACCAGCCCCGCCACCAUGCCCCGGCCCUGCACCUGACACCAUUGAUCUGACCCUGCAGCCACCUCCACCAGUCAGUGAGCCUGCCCCACCAAAGAAAGAUGGUGCCAUCUCAGACAAUACUAAGGCUGCCCUUAAAGCUGCCCUGCUCAAGUCUUUGAGGAGCCGGCUCAGAGAUGGCCCCAGCGCACCCCUGGAGGCUCCUGAGCCUCGGAAGCCGGUGACAGCCCAGGAGCGCCAGCGGGAGCGGGAGGAGAAGCGGCGGAGGCGGCAAGAACGAGCCAAGGAGCGGGAGAAACGGCGGCAGGAGCGGGAGCGAAAGGAACGGGGGGCUGGGGCCUCUGGGGGCCCCUCCACUGACCCCUUGGCUGGACUAGUGCUCAGUGACAAUGACAGAAGCCUGUUGGAACGCUGGACUCGAAUGGCCCGGCCCGCAGCCCCAGCCCUCACCUCUGUGCCGGCCCCUGCCCCAGCGCCAACGCCAACCCCAACCCCAGUCCAACCUACCAGUCCUCCUCCUGGCCCUGUAGCCCAGCCCACUGGCCCGCAACCACAAUCUGCGGGCUCUACCUCUGGCCCUGUACCCCAGCCUGCCUGCCCACCCCCUGGCCCUGCACCCCACCCCACUGGCCCUCCUGGGCCCAUCCCUGUCCCCGCGCCACCCCAGAUUGCCACCUCCACCAGCCUCCUGGCUGCCCAGUCACUUGUGCCACCCCCUGGGCUGCCUGGCUCCAGCACCCCAGGAGUUUUGCCUUACUUCCCACCUGGCCUGCCGCCCCCAGACGCCGGGGGAGCCCCUCAGUCUUCCAUGUCAGAGUCACCUGAUGUCAACCUUGUGACCCAGCAGCUAUCUAAGUCACAGGUGGAGGACCCCCUGCCCCCUGUGUUCUCAGGCACACCAAAGGGCAGUGGGGCUGGCUACGGUGUUGGCUUUGACCUGGAGGAAUUCUUAAACCAGUCUUUCGACAUGGGCGUGGCUGAUGGGCCACAGGAUGGCCAGGCAGAUUCAGCCUCUCUCUCAGCCUCCCUGCUUGCUGACUGGCUCGAAGGCCAUGGCAUGAACCCUGCCGAUAUUGAGUCCCUGCAGCGUGAGAUCCAGAUGGACUCCCCAAUGCUGCUGGCUGACCUGCCUGACCUCCAGGACCCCUGAGGCCCCCAGCCUGUGCCUUGCUGCCACAGUAGACCUAGUUCCAGGAUCCAUGGGAGCAUUCUCAAAGGCUUUAGCCCUGGACCCAGCAGGUGAGGCUCGGCUUGGAUUAUUCUGCAGGUUCAUCUCAGACCCACCUUUCAGCCUUAAGCAGCCACCUGAGCCACCACCGAGCCAUGGCAGGAUCGGGAGACCCCAACUCCCCCUGAACAAUCCUUUUCAGUAUUAUAUUUUUAUUAUUAUUAUGUUAUUAUUACACUGUCUUUUUGCCAUCAAAAUGAGGCCUGUGAAAUACAAGGUUCCCUUCUGCACCUGA